AAGACUUGGCGAAGCGCUGCGCUCGCGCCCGGAUCCCUCAGGCGGCUGCAGGCUUCAGCCUGCGCUGGUUGGUGAAACAGAGAUGUCAGAAAAGGAGAACAACUUCCCGCCACUGCCCAAGUUCAUCCCUGUGAAGCCCUGCUUCUACCAGAACUUCUCCGACGAGAUCCCAGUGGAGCACCAGGUCCUGGUGAAGAGGAUCUACCGGCUGUGGAUGUUUUACUGCGCCACCCUCGGCGUCAACCUCAUUGCCUGCCUGGCCUGGUGGAUCGGCGGAGGCUCGGGGACCAACUUCGGCCUGGCCUUCGUGUGGCUGCUCCUGUUCACGCCUUGCGGCUACGUGUGCUGGUUCCGGCCUGUCUACAAGGCCUUCCGAGCCGACAGCUCCUUUAAUUUCAUGGCGUUUUUCUUCAUCUUCGGAGCCCAGUUUGUCCUGACCGUCAUCCAGGCGAUUGGCUUCUCCGGCUGGGGCGCGUGCGGCUGGCUGUCGGCAAUUGGAUUCUUCCAGUACAGCCCGGGCGCUGCCGUGGUCAUGCUGCUUCCAGCCAUCAUGUUCUCCGUGUCGGCUGCCAUGAUGGCCAUCGCGAUCAUGAAGGUGCACAGGAUCUACCGAGGGGCUGGCGGAAGCUUCCAGAAGGCACAGACGGAGUGGAACACGGGCACUUGGCGGAACCCACCGUCGAGGGAGGCCCAGUACAACAACUUCUCAGGCAACAGCCUGCCCGAGUACCCCACUGUGCCCAGCUACCCGGGCAGUGGCCAGUGGCCUUAGAGGGAGCCUGCCCUGCCCCCACCGCCCACCACCUCCUCCCCUUCAUUCCUGCUGCUACCCCUGGUCCCGAGGGCUGGGAGUACCUGGGGCCCCAUCCCCCCAGCUGGGAUGGUGGAAGCCGGUGGUGGCCACGGACCGCCCCCCUCCUGCCAGGGCCACAGAACCCGUGUUCAUCUCAUCCGAGAGCGGAGUUCCUCACAAGCACUCCCCAGCAGCCCUUGGCCUCUGCCGUCCACAGGACGCCCUCUUGCUCCCGGAAACGUGUGGUCACCCGCCGUCCACUGCACGGCUGGUACGGCCUUGUCUUCAGGUCUCGAGGCCUGACUCCGGGGGACAGGUGGCAGCAGGUCGGCCGCCCUCCCGUCCUCCCAGAGCUGCUGGCGCUGAGGUCAGAGCGGGUCUGAUGGGGAGCUCCGUCUCACCGGCCACCCGCCGUCACCAUGGCAGAUGCCCUUGGCCGGAACUAAUAAGAGGCGUCGGGGCCAGCUUCCGGUCCCCUGCAGUGAUAGAGGGCUUGGUGCCUAGCUGAGUCCUCGCUGUCCCCGCCAUCCCCUGAUCUGUGCGGCUCCAGCCUCGCCCCCUCCCCACGUGCACCAUACCUGGGGAGUUCCUGGUCCAGGGUAUCCUGGGGCCACCCUCCCUGCCUCCAAAACAGGGAUCCCUGGCAGGCUGUCUUUCCACGCCCCUGAGUUCAGAGUCGGGGACCCAGGCCAGGUCGGGAGCACAGCCGCUCCCCAAACCCAGCAAACCGGCAGAGAGCCGGUUUCCCAGCAGCCGGAGCCCUGCAGGAGAGGCCUUUGUGUUUUGUUUUGUUUUGUUUUUUCUCUUUUGAGACAAGAGUUUCACUCUGUCGCCCAGGCUGGAGUGCAGUGGUGUGAUCUCGGCUCACUGCAACCUCUGCCUCCCGUGUUCAAGCAGUUCUCCUGCCUCAGCCUCCCAAAUAGCUGGGAUUACAGUUGCCUGCCACCACGCCCAGCUAAUUUUUAUAUUUUUAGUACAGAUGGGGUUUCACCAUGUUGGCCAGGCUGGUCUCGAACUCCUGACCUCAAGUGAUCCACCCGCCUUGGCCUCCCAAAGUGCUGGGAUAAUAGGUGUCAGCCACCGCGCCCAGCCUGGAGUGGCCUUUUAUGAGAGGGGACCCGUCAAAUCUGUGCCUUAUGGAGGGGUCCGGCAGCGGCCACAAUUGUCUUGUCCCCUCACCCCCCAACUCCCCCUGGAACACCUCUCCCAGGCAAGACAUUUUCACAGCACCAUUCACAACGGUUGGGCCAAAAAGAAACUUUUCCUUCAUCAUUUCCUGCACUCGCUGACCACAACUUUGGACACCCCAGGCUGCCACCCCUCCCCACCCGUUCACCCCCAGGAUGCUGUUGCUGUAGGACGCCUGCUGCCCUGGAGCCCUCCCCAGGAUGUGAGCCAGUCCCCUCGCUGGUACGGAAUGCCGCUGGGUGCCCGGAGGCGGCCAUGGUGUCUCGAUGGACGGCAGCCAGGAUGGAGCACCCAUGGGUCUCACGGCCAUGCUUCAGGGUCUUCAGGUCCUGCCCCCGGCCAGUCUGCCAAGAGGCACCCCCUUCCCCAGCCUCUCGCCUGCACUGAUGCAGACAAAAUCUCACCUGGCAGGCCCAACCCCCCCCCACCCCUCCCCCGCCGUGUGUGGCCCCUCGCCGCAUCGUUGGGGUUUUGUUAUGUGAAAAUAUCCUGGAAAUAAAUACAUGUUUCUGCACUUAGA